AGAUUGGCAUGUACUACCAGCCGCAGGCAGAGGUUAGGGGUAGCUGAUGUUUGCACCCGAGGAGGCUUUGCUAAGAAACAUCCCCUUAGUCAUACCACACCCAAGUAUAAUUGAUCUAGGAGUUUAUCUAAAAUAGUAGCUCCUAAGAGACUUGGAAAGUGUGCUAAUUUCUUCGAAAUUUCUUUAGAAUAAUUCACAUUCUUCCCCAUAUCGCUUAUGGAGCCGUCCUAACUGCUGACCUUUUCAAGAUGGCGGUCCGCGGGCGACACUCUCGGGCUCGCGCACCUCCCCAAGAUGGCGGCGCCCGAGGCCUGGCGCGCCCGGAGUUGCUGGUUCUGUGAGGUAGCGGCGGCAACGACCAUGGAGGCCACGUCCCGGGAGGCGGCGCCAGCGAAGAGCUCGGCCUCGGGCCCCAACGCUCCCCCCGCCCUGUUCGAGCUGUGCGGGCGGGCGGUGAGCGCCCAUAUGGGGGUUCUGGAGAGCGGGGUGUGGGCCCUCCCAGGCCCAAUACUUCAAAGCAUCCUACCUCUGCUCAAUAUAUAUUACUUGGAGAGGAUUGAGGAAACUGCCCUCAAGAAAGGCCUCUCAACUCAGGCCAUCUGGCGCCGACUCUGGGAUGAACUGAUGAAGACAAGGCCUUCCAGUUUGGAAAGUGUGACAUGUUGGCGAGCCAAGUUUAUGGAGGCCUUUUUUUCCCAUGUUCUACGUGGGACCAUUGAUGUGUCUUCUGACAGGCGUCUUUGUGAUCAGCGGUUCUCACCUCUUCUGCACAGCUCCCGCCAUGUCCGACAGCUCACCAUCUGUAACAUGCUGCAGGGUGCAACCGAGCUGGUGGCUGAGCCCAACCGCAGGGUUCUGGAGACCCUGGCCAGCUCCCUGCACACUCUCAAGUUCCGCCACCUGCUGUUCUCUGAUGUGGCUGCUCAGCAGUCACUUCGGCAGCUGUUGCAUCAGCUCAUUCACCAUGGGGCUGUCAGUCAAGUGUCGCUAUACUCCUGGCCUGUGCCUGAGUCAGCCCUUUUCAUCCUUAUUCUCACCAUGAGUGCUGGCUUCUGGCAACCAGGGCCUGGUGGCCCACCCUGCCGCCUCUGUGGAGAGGCCUCCCGAGGCCGGGCCCCAUCCCGAGAUGAAGGGUCCCUCUUAUUGGGCUCACGUCGGCCCCGCCGGGAUGCUGCUGAGCGAUGUGCUGCAGCCCUGAUGGCCAGCCGGCGUAAGAGUGAAGCCAAGCAGAUGCCCAGAGCUGCACCUGCCACUCGGGUAACACGCCGGAGCACACAGGAGAGCCUGACAGCAGGCGGAACAGACCUUAAGAGGGAGCUGCACCCCCCAGCCACCUCCCAUGAGGCUCCUGGCACCAAGCGGUCACCUUCUGCUCCAGCAGCCACCUCCUCUGCCUCUUCUUCUACAUCCUCAUACAAACGGGCACCAGCUAGCUCAGCCCCACAGCCUAAGCCCCUAAAGCGUUUCAAGCGAGCUGCAGGGAAGAAGGGUGCUCGCACCCGUCAGGGGCCUGGUGCAGAGUCUGAAGACCUGUAUGACUUCGUUUUUAUUGUGGCUGGCGAGAAGGAGGAUGGCGAAGAGAUGGAGAUUGGGGAAGUGGCUUGUGGAGCUUUGGAUGGAUCAGAUCCCAGCUGCCUGGGGCUUCCAGCACUGGAAGCUUCACAAAGAUUCCGCAGCAUCUCCACCUUGGAGCUAUUCACAGUUCCACUCUCCACAGAGGCAGCCCUGACACUAUGCCACCUGCUGAGCUCCUGGGUGUCACUGGAGAGCCUCACACUCUCCUACAAUGGCCUGGGCUCUAACAUCUUCCGCCUGCUAGACAGCCUGCGGGCCCUGUCAGGCCAGGCUGGAUGUCGCCUCCGUGCCCUGCAUCUCAGUGACCUGUUCUCACCACUGCCCAUCCUGGAGCUGACACGUGCUAUCGUGCGAGCACUGCCCCUGCUACGGGUCCUCUCUAUUCGUGUUGACCACCCAAGCCAGCGGGACAACCCUGGUGUGCCAGGGAAUGCAGGGCCCCCUAGCCACAUAAUAGGCGAUGAGGAGAUACCAGAAAACUGCCUGGAGCAGUUGGAGAUGGGAUUUCCACGGGGAGCCCAGCCAGCCCCACUGCUGUGCUCCGUUCUGAAGGCCUCGGGUUCUCUGCAGCAGCUGUCCCUGGAUAGUGCCACCUUUGCCUCUCCCCAGGAUUUUGGGCUUGUUUUGCAAACACUCAAAGAGUACAACCUAGCCCUGAAAAGACUGAGCUUCCAUGACAUGAAUCUCGCUGACUGUCAGAGCGAGGUGCUCUUUUUGCUACAGAAUCUGACUCUGCAAGAGAUUACCUUCUCCUUCUGCCGUCUGUUUGAGAAGCGCCCAGCCCAAUUUCUGCCUGAGAUGGUUGCUGCUAUGAAGGGCAACUCCACACUGAAGGGCCUCCGGCUGCCAGGGAACCGCCUGGGGAAUGCUGGCCUGCUGGCCUUGGCAGAUGUUUUCUCAGAGGAUUCAUCCUCCUCUCUCUGUCAGCUGGACAUCAGUUCCAACUGCAUCAAGCCAGAUGGGCUUCUGGAGUUCGCCAAGCGGCUGGAGCGCUGGGGCCGUGGAGCCUUUGGUCACCUGCGCCUCUUCCAAAACUGGCUGGACCAGGAUGCAGUCACAGCCAGGGAAGCCAUCCGGCGGCUCCGGGCUACCUGCCAUGUGGUUAGCGACUCAUGGGACUCAUCCCAGGCCUUCGCAGAUUAUGUUAGCACCAUGUGAUGGGGCCCGUACCUCACAGUCUCAUGCUCGGUACCAUCAGCUUGCAGGGGCUGAAGCAUGGGCUGCCCAGAACCCCAACCACCAGUUCUAUCUUUCUCUUUCUGUCACCUUUUUUCUCUUUUUUCCUUCUUCCCUUGCACUGAGGUCCUGGAGGCCUUGAUGAGGCCCAGCAAACAGGCAUUCUCACAGCUGGGUUUAUAGUCUUUGGGCCCCUUACUCAGUAUCCUGGGAACCCUGGGCCAGGAGGUUACAGUGGUCAUCAUAAUUGCUGAAGAGAUCCCCUCCCCUGCCCCUGGGUUCCUGCCUUCCCUCCUCAAGCAGGCACCCAGGCUUUAGAGAAGUAUAGGGGGCUUCUUCCCUGCUGGGCUUACCACACUGCUCUCAGGCCUCAAACCCUUUCAUACCUUUAUUCUUUUUUUUAACCAAAAAAGUUUUUCUUAUAAAAUAAAUUUUGGGCAAACAUCAUGCAGCCCUUCUUGAUGAUUUUCUCCCAGAGAACAAAAUUCAACAGGGCCCUGUGGAGCAAGGAGCCCCUUUUCCCUAUCUCCUUCCUCUAAGAGCUACACCCAGACCAGCUGGUUAUCAGCGGAGGCCCCGCUGCUCCUCAUGAGAACGCUGGUGGAAGACGAAGGUGAUGGCAGUGGAGGCAGCAUCCCAGGCAGCCUGGAGUACCUCAUCCCGGAGCCCCCACUUAUCAGUGCAGUGGUUCCACCCUGCCAGGUCUGAAGUGCAGUCAGAACCAUCAGGGGGUGGCCGGAUCUGACGGCUGUUGACACAACGUCGGCAGUGCAACCUAGGGACAGAAGGCACAGCUGAAGUCACUACAGAUCCCAUCUCCCUACUGUGUGGGUAGCUUAGAGAUAAUGGUUAGGGCACUUCCCCACCUGUCAUGUGUGUCACUGAGGCUAGCUUCAUCCAGGAUAAACAGCUCCUUCAACUCGCCCAGAGAGAAGUGGCGCUCUACAUCCUGCUCCUCAUCCACCACACAGCUGCUCAGUGCCUUCUUGUGGCUCUGACGCUGGAAGAUCUUCUCCUCAAUGGUCCCUGCCUGGGGAAGAGGAGGUGGGGAAUGUCAAAAGAUACAGCGCUUAGCCAUCCUCAUAAAAAGGGAGCAGGAAAACCAAAGGGUUGAAACUACAGCUACCCGAGAAGAGGAGAUGAAUAAAAAGUAUGAGUCCCAGAACAUUAUCUCUACUCAGCUGAGGUCCAUUUUCCCAGUCUGUCUCCUGAGAACAUGACAUGAAUAGUCUGCCCACCCAGGCUACUUUCUAUACUAAUGAAGGGUCCCAGGGCCUGGCUAAAUCCCGUCAGGGUGAACUGAGGUUUGUCUGCUGCAGCUUCAGAUUUCUGCACCAAGCCCAACUCUAACUCAUUCAAUAAAUAUCAUUUAGGUAUCUAUUCUA